CCUGGCUUAGGCUGGGAGGCACAGCGCCCGUGUGCUGGAGGCGAGUUGGCUCCGGGUGGGGGAGGCUGGGGUUCCAAACCAGGGCAGGGGAAUGGUGGCCCUGCGUGGCUCGUGGACCUCUCUCAGGGACCCCUCUCAGCAGGGGCCGGAAAAGCAGGCCCACACCCAGUGGUCAUUGCAGGAACUUCACUUGAGCUGGUCUGCUUGUGAGCCUGUGGUUUGGAGAGGAGAAGACGCACUUCCCCAUGAGAAAAAGGUGGUCAUCCCCAUGGGCUCCACAGAUGAGGACACCGGCCCUCAGCUCUGCCCCCUCUCAGAAGCCUUCCUCACCUGGGGGUUCUGGGUGAAGGGAGCUCCCCGCCAGAGACUCAUGUGGGAUCGUGUGUGGACCGUAGAGCCACAGAGCGUCAUCUGUAAGCCAGUUUAGAUCCAGGCUUUAACUUCAGUUUCCUGUGUGACCUUUGAGAAGCCAUCCCUCCAAGUGCUUCCUUUGAAGGGUGAGCCCUGGGUGCCUCUCUCUGAGGGAGGCCCUUGCUCCAUCUGGGCUUGACUGUGCCACGGGGGAUCAGAAGCAACAUACAUUCUGUCAGCAGCUGCCGGAAAUGCUGGAGCAGCAGUCCUGGAGGCGGGGUGAAGCAGUCCCUGGCUUUUGGAGGAGGCGUGAGAAGAAAUUCAUGGGGGGCUUUAAUUCUUUUCAGAUUCCCAACCAUUUUCUUCUAGCUGCUACUGCCUGCAUUUGUGUAACUUAGUUUGCAACACAGGUGACAA